CCAUUUUUGGUCUUGUUAGCUUUAAUACCUGAAAAAACCUUACAUUAAAUUGCCCAUUUCACUUGGAUGGAAUAUAAUUUCACUUCUCCAUAUGCCCAGAUGUAUUACAUAGCACAUUAUCUACAUCGAUAAGAAUGAAUGGCUGACUUCUCUCACUCAUCUUCAGUCCUAAAUGCAGCAAAUGCUGCCGGUGCCCUGUCCAUCUCCCCUUGGCACUCACCAUUCUGUACACACAGACAGAGUAUUACCGCAAGCACCUGUGACUUUGUCUGAGGGCAUCCUCGAGCCAAAUCAGCAUGGGUGGCCCCUGUAUGUGGCAACCAGAAGUGUCAGGGAAUAAUGCUCCCAGGACUGUCCUCAGUCUAUGAGAAAGAAAAGUGGAUGAAUAAAUACCCCAGCUUCCUUGCAUCUAGGACGGGACAAUCUGAGGCUUAUUCUGUACUGUCUUCCAAGGUCCCCAGCAUGGACCAGUUGUCUGGAGCCGCUUGUGCUCAGGAAUACGUCUCUCAUUGUCUGUUUUCCUAUCCCUGACUCAGCUCCCCUUUCUGUCACCAAUGCUUCUAAGGAUUAGCACCCAAAGAAACUACUCCCACUCAAAUCCUCUCCUCCGGGAAUGCUUUUGGGGAAACCCAAGUGAAGACAGGGGCAAUUCGCCAGCUGAAGAUCGAGUCCAUCCCAUGGCAGGGUGGGCAGAUAUACCUCUCUAAUAAGUGAGAUGCACCCUGGGAUAUCAGCGGAGGGAGGGGCAGAAUUUAGAUCACACUCAUGAGUCAGAAAAACAGGCUAUGGAGUAGUUCUCCCCAGAAAAACAUUAUUGAUCUUGUCCAAUAAAACAAACAAAACCAAACAAACUGGGAGAUUUCAAGGCAACAAAGUUAAUGGAAAACAAUGUCCCAUAAAUUACCUAAGACUGAAUGAUAUUGCUGCAAAUCCAUCUUUAGGAUCUUAGCUAAGGUCUACAGUUUACUCUAAUCAUUGAAAAUUUAUUGCCAUCACCUGGAACAAUUGUUCUCGUCCUUAUCAGGUGCAAAUCACCUUGUAGAAAUGAAUGGUUUCAUGUCUCUCUACCAUCCUGACCUGCAAUCCAUAGACAAUGUAAUGACCCACCACGUAAUUUUUUAAUCUGUAAGUGCCCUAACUCAACACAUGGAGAAAUAAAGGUGAGUAAUUAUGUAAAUGAACGUCAGGUACUGAUGCAUCUACAUGAACACCCCCAGGCGGGAGCUCACUCGACGACGACAGGAAGAAUCCUGAUGCUUGCCACAAAUCUGUGGCGUCUCUGGGCAUGGAAGCACUGCUACCGCGGGCUCAUUCCGCAGCCCAGUGGCUGACAGAUACCAACAGCAGCCUUGCAACUGAUGGCAAGAGAUUCCAAAAGUGCCAACAAUUGUUGAAGUUUCCACCAAGAUCAGUGACAACUUCCCAUGAUUUCCCGACAGCGGCAUUCCUGUGGAAACUGAUGUCUAUGCACGGUGCGAAAGAUACAUCUAUACCGUCAUUGGUGGCUUAUGCUUUUGCAUGUAUGCUUUCAAGGUGAAAUGGCAAGUAGUCGAGUGCAAGUGCGGGCAGCAGACCCGGAAGUGCGGUGGGUGAGCCUUGCGCCCAGGAGGCUAGAGAUGCAGGAGCCCCAGAACCUGCGGUGCAGCGAGUGCACAUGCGCAUAGACGGGGCCCAGGAGCUGACCCUGGCCCUCCCGUUCGCUUCCGGUGUAGCAUGCAGAGACGUGAAGCCCGGGCCACGACGACGACCCCUCAGGUACCGAUGUUUUCAGAAACCCUCAAACAGAUUGGGUAGCGCUUCCCUGGGGGCAGGUUUCUGGGCAGGUGCCCAGACGCGCCUAGAAGCUGACCCCGGCCCUCCCGCUCACUUCCGUUCCAGGCCGCAGAGACGCGAAGUCCGGCCACGACGACGACCCCUCAGGUACCCAUGUUUUCAGAAACCCUCAAACAGAUUGGGUAGCGCUUCCCUGGGGGCGGGUUUCUGGGCAGAUGCCCACGUUGAACUCAGUGUGGACUUGUGGCAUCUUGCGGGCCUGUAGAUUAAUAUGACAGCCGUGAUUCCACCCUGCUUCACCAACGCACAUGCGUUUUCUCUCCUCUUAGGGGCCCUGUUUUCUGUUACAAUGGAUCGAGAUUUAGAACAGGCUCUGGAUCGCGCAGAGAAUAUCAUUGAAAUUGCCCAACAGAGACCUCCUAGAAGGAGAUACUCACCUAGGGCGGGAAAAACUCUGCAGGAAAAACUUUAUGACAUUUAUGUUGAAGAAUGUGGAAAAGAGCCUGAGGAUCCUCAGGAAUUGAGAAGCAAUGUAAACUUGUUAGAAAAGCUUGUUAGGAGAGAGUCCUUGCCAUGUUUACUGGUCAAUCUAUACCCAGGCAAUCAGGGGUAUUCUGUGAUGCUCCAGAGAGAAGAUGGGUCCUUUGCAGAGACCAUUCGGCUGCCUUAUGAAGAAAGGGCAUUGCUGGACUACUUGGAUGCAGAAGAAUUACCCCCUGCUUUGGGUGAUGUCCUGGAUAAAGCUUCGGUUAACAUUUUUCAUAGUGGGUGUGUCAUAGUAGAAGUUCGUGACUACAGGCAGUCCAGUAAUAUGCAACCUCCUGGUUACCAAAGCAGGCAUAUUCUUCUACGUCCAACGAUGCAGACUUUAGCCCAUGAUGUGAAGAUGAUGACAAGAGAUGGCCAGAAAUGGAGCCAGGAAGACAAGCUUCAGCUUGAGAGCCAGCUGAUCUUAGCGACAGCUGAACCACUGUGUCUUGAUCCUUCUGUAGCAGUUGCCUGCACUGCAAACAGGCUGCUGUACAACAAGCAAAAGAUGAAUACCGACCCGAUGAAACGGUGCCUCCAGAGGUAUUCGUGGCCCUCUGUAAAGCCACAGCAGGAGCAGUCUGACUGUCCACCUCCUCCUGAGCUGAGAGUGUCGACUUCUGGCCAAAAAGAAGAAAGAAAAGUAGGUCAGCCUUGUGAGCUGAACAUUGCUAAAGCAGGAAGUUGUGUAGACACGUGGAAAGGCAGACCCUGUGAUUUGGCCGUGCCUUCAGAAGUGGAUGUGGAGAAACUUGCUAAAGGGUAUCAGUCCGUCACAGCUGCUGACCCACAGCUCCCAGUCUGGCCAGCCCAGGAGGUAGAAGACCCUUUUGGAUUUGCGUUGGAAGCUGGCUGUCAGGCCUGGGACACCAAGCCAAGCAUCAUGCAGUCGUUUAAUGAUCCGCUUCUCUGUGGUAAAAUACGGCCACGUAAAAAAGCCAGGCAGAAGAGCCAGAAGUCUCCCUGGCAGCCCUUCCCAGAUGACCAUUCAGCUUGUCUCAGGCCUGGGUCAGAGACUGAUGCUGGGAGGGCAGUGAGUCAGGCCCAGGAAUCGGUGCAGAGCAAAGUCAAAGGUCCAGGCAAGAUGUCACACAGCUCCAGUGGCCCAGCCAGUGUCAGUCAGCUCUCUUCAUGGAAAACACCAGAACAGCCUGAUCCUGUGUGGGUCCAGUCUUCAGUAUCGGGGAAGGGAGAGAAACAUCCACCUCCCCGCACCCAACUUCCCUCAAGCUCAGGAAAGAUUUCCUCAGGUAACAGUUUUCCCCCACAACAGGCAGGCAGCCCUCUUAAGCGUCCAUUUUCUGCUGCUGCUGCUAUUGCUGCUGCUGCUGCUGCUGCUGCUGCUGCUGCUGCUGCUGCUGCUGCUGCUGCUCCUGCUCCUGCUCUAGCUGCUGCUGCUGCUCCUGCUCUAGCUGCUGCUGCUGCUCCUGCUCUAGCUGCUGCUGCUGCUCCUGCUCCUGCUCCUGCCGCUGCUCCUGCUGUAGCUGCUGCUCCUGCUGCUGCUGCUUCUGCGGCACCAAGUCAUUCUCAGAAGCCCUCUGUGCCUCUCAUUCAAGCUAGCAGGCCCUGUCCAGCUGCCCAGCCCCCCACCAAAUUCAUAAAAAUAGCGCCAGCCAUUCAGUUGAGGACAGGCUCCACUGGCCUAAAGGCCAUCAAUGUGGAGGGCCCAGUCCAGGGAGCCCAGGCUUUGGGGAGCAGUUUCAAGCCUGUGCAGGCCCCUGGCUCGGGUGCCCCCGCUCCUGCAGGAAUCAGUGGCAGUGACCUUCAGUCCUCAGGAGGUCCACUACCAGAUGCAAGGCCCGGUGCAGUGCAGGCAUCUUCUCCAGCACCCCUUCAGUUUUUCCUAAAUACUCCGGAAGGUCUCAGGCCUCUGACACUCCUCCAGGUUCCGCAGGGCUCGGCGGUUCUGACCGGCCCGCAGCAGCAGUCCCAUCAGCUGGUUUCCCUGCAGCAGCUCCAGCAGCCCACAGCUGCUCAUCCUCCUCAGCCAGGGCCACAGGGUUCCGCACUAGGUUUGAGCACGCAAGGGCAGGCCUUCCCUGCUCAGCAACUUCUUAAGGUGAACCCCACUAGAGCCAGAAGUGGUCUGCAGCCCCAGCCCCAGCCUGCUGUGUUGAGUCUGCUUGGCUCUGCCCAGGUUCCUCAGCAGGGUGUCCAGCUCCCCUCUGUCUUGAGGCAGCAGCAGCCACAGCCACAGCCGCCGAAGCUGCAACUGCAACCGCAGUGGCAGCCAAAGCCACGGCAGGAGCAGCCACAGUCGCAGCAGCAGCAGCCGCAGCAUAUCCAGCUCCAGACUCAGCAGUUGAGAGUCUUGCAGCAGCCGCAGCAUAUCCAGCUCCAGACUCAGCAGUUGAGAGUCCUGCAGCAGCCAGUGUUUUUGGCAACAGGCGCUGUUCAGAUAGUGCAGCCACAUCCAGGUGUGCAAGUAGGGAGCCAGUUGGUAGAUCAGAGGAAGGAAGGCAAGCCAACCCCUCCAGCGCCCUGAGGCUUGUGGUAGUUUGUCUCUCUUUUAAAAGCACAGGAGCAUUGACUCAAAUGAUUUCCCAGUUUUUACUUGAGUUUUGUUUUUUUUUUCAUGUUUCGGUAUUUUACAUUUUAAAGUACACAGUUUACACAGAAGCACAAUCCACUGAUUUUUCUUUAGAAACGGAAGUGAUUUCCUAAAGGAGCGUUGUUUUGCUUAAGUUACUCUUUUUGUUGUCAUUGCUGCUGUCGAUAUAAUUAUUUUUAAUAUAGUGUUUUAAAGUGUCCAAAUCCCAACCAGUUUGAGUCUAAACUCGUGAAACGUAUAAUUUCUCUAAAGCCGUAAAAUGGCAAUACCAACAAUAUUAAGUUAAUAUUUUAACAAGAUUUUAAUUUUAAGUUAAUAUUUUAACAAGAAGAGUGGGAUUAAAUUUAUUUUAAUGGUGGUAAAAACAUAUAAUCUAAAAUGGACCACCUUCACUAUUUUAAGUGCCCAGUGCAAUAGUAUUAAGUCCAUCCCCACGGUUGUGCCGCAGAUCUCGAGACCAUCUUGCAACACUGAAACUCAUGCCCAUUGAACAGCAGCUCCCCAUUCUCCCUUGCCCAGUCCCUGGCAGCCAUUGUUCUACUUUCUUUCUCUAUGAGUUGACUACCCUGGCCACUUCAUGGAAGUGGAAUCAUAUGGCAUUUGUCAUUUGAUGAGUGUCUUAUCUCACUUGGCAUAAUGUCCUCAUGAUCUAUCCCUGCUGUCUCAUGUGACAUAAAGGUCAUUGCUUUUUAAAAAUGGUUUCCCUGUACAUAAUAUAUAUGAAAGUGACUUAUGAAUUCUGAGAAACCUCUUUCAGAAGAAUUCUGAAAGAGUGUAAUCGUAUUUAGAUUAAUAGGUUUAUGUACAAUAUAUGGAAUGGAAUUAUUACACAUUCAUUUUGAAAAAUGAAAUGAAAAAGUACAAUACAGUGAUCCUUGUCACACUGCGAUUGAAUACAUGGAAGACCUCUAAAGCUGUGGAAUGGAAUUAGUGGCAGAUUUGCUUGUGACAGUCCCCUGCCCUUUCAAAGGCCCUGUCUGCACCUAGUGCUCCACAGAGCAAGGCUUUCUCACUGGCUUUGAAAAGGCUCUUUUUGGAUGUUUUGUGUGCUCUCUUUAUAAAAUCAUUUACAUUUUUUGUAGGUUGUUUGCAAGAAACAUUUAGUGAAACAUUUGAAAAUCCAUUUUAUUGGUUUGCUUUUCAAAUAUCUGUAGCCUUGUUUCUUAAGUAGAACCCCCGUCUUUUUCUUUGUCUUUUUCUCUUUGUUGAUGCAUCAUCAUCAGUUGUUCAUCUGUUUCUGCUCCCUCAUUUUUUCCCUUGUUCCAGUGAGACUCAAAGAACCAUGAACUUUUGUGCCCCUUUGUCUUCCCUUUCUUUUUUCUUUUUUAACAACUAAGGGGUAAUCACAGAACAACCAACCAUUGUAAAGUACAAUUGUAAAGUGGCAUUUAGUACAUUCAUGAUGUUGUACAACUACCCCUUCUGUUUCCAAAACAUUUUCAUCACCCACCAAGCAAUCUCUGUACCCAUUAAGCACUAGCGUGACAUCUUCACACUCCCAGCCUCUGGCAACCACCAAUUUGCUUUCUGUUUCUAUGGAUUUACCUAAAUAUCUCCUGUAAAUGUAGUCAUACAGUAUGUGAUCUUUUGUGUCUGGCCUCUUUCACUCGGCAUAAUGUUUUUGAAGUUCAUCUAUGUUGUAAAAUGUAUUGCUAAUUCAUUCCUAUCUGUGGUUCAAUAACAUUCCAUUGUUUGUAUGUAGCAGAUUUUGUACAUUCAUCCGAUGAUAGACAGUUGGUUUUUGUCUGCCUUUUGGCUGUCGUGCAUAGGGCUGCUGUCAACAUUUGUGUAGAAGUAUUUGUUUUAGUGCCUCUUAUAUUUUGCUCUGUUACAGCUUUGAAGGGUACCAUGUUUAUAUAAUAUUUGUUUUUCUAAGUAUACAUGUAUGUUUCUCUGCCUUUUGCCUUAACGAAAUGAAAAGAAGUUUGGUCUGGCAGUUCCAAAAGACAUCAGUGAAGAGGCAGGUAACUGGUUAAUCUUACUUGACAAAACCUAUUACUAAUGUGCUACUGAUGCUGUUAAAGAAAGACUUGGCCAACUUCAAGAAAACACAUCGAAUUUCCUGAGUGACACCAAGUCCAUCAGAUCAUCCUGGGCAUAAUUGGAAAUGGUGCCUGCACUUUUAAGAAGCGAACCAGUGCAACGACUGGUUGCAAAGAAGAGUUUCUCCUUAGCUUUGGGUGCCAACUAGAGACCUGAACUCAGAAUAUCAUCAGAUUUGGUCUACUUCCUUCCUUUGUUGUCUAUCUGGUCCUUUCAAGUACUACAUGGAGCUACCAGCCAAACUUGUGCUUGAGUGAUGUGGCUCUUUCCUCCCAGGCAGGCAAAUAAAUUCAGCUUUGUUUCAGA